GUAGUUCCGCCAUCGGACGGAAGCCGACCGGGGCGUGCGGAGGGAUGUGGCCCGGAAUAUUGGUAGGGGGGGCCCGGGUGGCGUCAUGCAGGUACCCCGCGCUGGGGCCUCGCCUCGCCGCUCACUUUCCAGCGCAGCGGCCGCCGCAGCGGACACUCCAGAACGGCCUGGCCCUGCAGCGGUGCCUGCACGCGACGGCGACCCGGGCUCUCCCGCUCAUUCCCAUCGUGGUGGAGCAGACGGUACGGCGGCCGGGCGGGGACACGGUUCGGGGGCUCCGGGCUGGGUGGGGAUCGGCUGGCUGCCCCGGCCCCUCACCUCCAUCUUUCUACCCCCAGGGUCGCGGCGAGCGCGCCUAUGACAUCUACUCGCGGCUGCUGCGGGAGCGCAUCGUGUGCGUCAUGGGCCCGAUCGAUGACAGCGUUGCCAGCCUUGUUAUCGCACAGCUCCUCUUCCUGCAAUCCGAGAGCAACAAGAAGCCCAUCCACAUGUACAUCAACAGCCCUGGUGGUGUGGUGACCGCGGGCCUGGCCAUCUACGACACGAUGCAGUACAUCCUCAACCCGAUCUGCACCUGGUGCGUGGGCCAGGCCGCCAGCAUGGGCUCCCUGCUUCUCGCCGCCGGCACCCCAGGCAUGCGCCACUCGCUCCCCAACUCCCGUAUCAUGAUCCACCAGCCCUCAGGAGGCGCCCGGGGCCAAGCCACAGACAUUGCCAUCCAGGCAGAGGAGAUCAUGAAGCUCAAGAAGCAGCUCUAUAACAUCUACGCCAAGCACACCAAACAGAGCCUGCAGGUGAUCGAGUCCGCCAUGGAGAGGGACCGCUACAUGAGCCCCAUGGAGGCCCAGGAGUUUGGCAUCUUAGACAAGGUUCUGGUCCACCCUCCCCAGGACGGUGAGGAUGAGCCCACGCUGGUGCAGAAGGAGCCUGUAGAAGCAGCGCCGGCAGCAGAACCUGUCCCAGCUAGCACCUGAGAGCUGGGCCUCCUCUCCAGAAUCAUGUGGAGGGGCCAGAGGCCUGCCAGACCCCCAGCUGGGCCCUGCUCACCCCUUGUUGCUGGGCUUGGAGGGGCCUCUUGAGGAACUUUUAAUUUGCAGGGGUGCCCGCUAUGGACGGGGCAUUCCAGCUGAGACACUGUGAUUUUAAAUUAAAUCUUUGUGGUCUUUGCUCUGCGUCUGGGACACCCUCCCUUCUGCACCAUGACAGCGUGUACACAUCUGUGUUUCACAGGCCCCUUCUGCUUUUGUCCUGACCCCAAGAGGCAAGCCAUGUCUUCCUUCAACAGAUUCUCCUGAUCAUAUCCUAUAUUCCAGGCAGUGUUCUUUUGUGAAGAAGACACAAGAAACCCUCCUCAAAAGAGCUCCAUUCUUGUGGCAGUAGACAGUUACUAAAAAAAACAAAACAGGCCAGGCGCGCUGGCUCACGCCUGUAAUCCCAGCACUUUGGGAGCCCGAGGCAGGCGGAUCAUGAGGUCAGGAGAUCGAGAACAUCCUGGCUAACAUGGUGAAACCCCAUUUCUACUAAAAAUACAAAAAUUAGCCGAGCGUGGUGCACCUGUAAUCCCAGCUACUCCGGAGGCUGAGGCAGAAGAAUUGCUUGAACUUAGGAGGUGGAGGUUGCAGUGAGCAGGAUCACGCCACUGCCCUUUAGCCUGGGCAACAGAGCAAGGCUCUGUCUCAAAAAAAAAAAAAAACAAAAACAGGAAAGGUGGCAUGCAAGUGUGAGGGUAAGCGUGUUACAGUUUUUUAUGGGGUAAUCAGGGAAGCCCUCACUGAGAAGGUGGUGGUUGAGCAAAGCCUCAAAGGAGGUGAGGGGUGGAGCCUGUGUCCAGGCAGAGGGCACAGCCAGUGCAAAGGCCCUGUGACAGGACUGUACCUGGCAUGUGAGGACCUAUGAGGAGGCCCGUGGCUGAGGGAAGGUGGAAGAGAGGAGAUCAAAAAGUAGAGGUGAAAAUUAGCCAGGCGUGAUGGUGCACUUGAACCCGGGAGGCAGAGGUUGCAGUGAGCCAAGAUCACGCCACUGCACUCCAGCCUGGGCAACAAAGCGAGAUUCUGUCUCCAAAAAAAAAAAAGUGGAGGUGAUUGAGAAUAGAUCAUAAAAGGCCUGACAUCUAAAAGGAGGGAUGUGAACCAUGGAGGGUUUUGAGAAGAGGAAGGAAAAUAAGGAUGACUAUGACUCCUGAGGAGUGCACCAUGAGCAGAAACUGGAGAGCAGUUAGGAUAGUUGGAGUAAUCUAGACGAAAGCUGAUGGCAGCCCUGGCCGAGUGAUGAGAAAAAGUCAGAUUCUAGCUAGGUGGGAUGUGACAGAGAGCAGUUUCCAGAAACUCCGAGCUGAUGGCCCAAAGCAGGAAGAUGGAGACCUGUCGCCUGAGAUGGGAAGUGUAGGCAAAGGAACAGGCUUGGGGAGGGAUCAGGAGUUGAUUUUGGAUAUAUUAUACCUGAUGUUUUGAUAUGUCCCUCGACAUCAGGGUCAAGAGGUUGAAAUAAAAACGUAGGUGUCAUCGGC